GUACAUGUACCACACAGACACACACACAAACACAAACACACACACCGCACACAUAUACAUACACACACAUACACAUACACACCACACACACACAUACACAUGCACAUACACACACACACACACACACACUUGUGUGCAGUUCUGCAGUUAACUAGAAAACUUGGGUAACUUUUUCAGACUUUGUCCUAAACUAAUUUGAUCAAGGAACUUUUUUUUAAGGAUAUGUACCACGUUUUGUAGAGUAGUGUUUUGUUUAAUGUACCACUCUGGAAAAUGCUUAUAAAGGCAUCGCUGGACUGAAUGUACUUCAGGAAAAUCAUCCAUAGAUACCAUUUGUUUCAAAAUUUGGUAAGAGUUAGGCGGCAGAGAGACUAAAUUCUCCACCAAGAUCUGGAGUGCAGAUAUUCUUUGUUGCUACUUAAAGGCAAAUCUGUCUGCCUCACACGUCACAUGAGUAGGGGUGACUUUGGUGAAUCCUAAGGCUGUACUGGAGCUUGUCACUUGGCUACACGUCUAUCUCAGACCUGCUGACAGGACCAGUGUAUUUCUACGGGGUUCUGGAUCAAGCAGUCCAGCCUCUUACUGGAUCGUGUCUCUCAAGUCAGCCUCUGUGGAGUUAUAUCCGCUUCCCCUGGGAUGCGGUGUGAGACCAGCACAUAGUGAGCAUGGACAUCACUAGAUUGAGUGAAAUGUUCCUGGGCUGUGGGGACUUCACGAGACCACAUCUAAUUUUUGCACAAAUAUCUGUCACUCACCACCUACCUGUGCUCGUCUGGUUGCUCGGUUGGGAUUUUUUGACAGGAAAUAGGAGACUUGGUUAAAUGUCUGUGUAACUUUGAGAUGCUUGAGGAGAGAGACACUUUGCACUGACCCCAACAGGUUUCCUUAUGCACCUGAUUACAACAAAGAAUCUCGGGUUCUUGCUUGGGAGAGUGGCUGAGCAGCUUUGCUGCACGUUGGCUUGUCCACCCAAGCUGGAAAAACCUGUGGUCCAGAGUCCCAGGGUGACUAAUGAACAUGUGUGUGACAAGGGAGAAAAAAGUUUGGGGCAAUAUUAUCUUUUGGGGAUAACUGCCUUUGAGGCUGUCUUCCUGGUUAUUUUGAGGAUGUGUGAUUCACAGAAGAGAGACGGACCUACACAUUGGUCAUCCUCAAGAUUUUCAGGGCCAUCCUAGAAUAGCCUCACCCUGGAUCCCAGGAACAGACCUCUUUAUCAAUAGUGGCAUUCCUUUACAUCCUCAGCUAAGUAUAGUUACAAUGAUUGCUUUAGAGCACUCUAAAAAGAGUGACUACAGUGGCUGUGUUUGCCUUUAUACUUUGAAAAAAGAAUGUCCACAACAACAAAUAUUUAUGAAGCUUUAUAAUUAAAAAAUACGUUCUUUAGCUAGAGACUGCUAAUGUUGAAAAGACCACCCCCACCUCCCCUCCUCAUUUUACCAAUGAGGAAACUGAGGGCUUAGGGUCAGAUAAAUUCAUCGAAAGCUCCCUACUAGGGGAUGAGCUGAGAUUAUAUCUUGAGUCCUCUUGAAGGAAGCUAGUCUGACACACGUAUGUUCCCCAUAGGGCCGUCACAUUCUUAUGGUCACACUAUACUCAGAUGCCGUAUUAGUCUGUUCUCAUGCUGCUAUAAGGACAAACCCAAGACUGGGUAAUUUAUAGAGGAGAGAGGUUUAAUGGACUCACAGUUCCAUGUGGCUGGGGAGGCCUCACAAUCAUGGUGGAAGGGGAAGAAGGAGCAAAGGCAUGUCUUACAUGGCAGCAGGCAAGACAGUGUGUGCAGGGGAAAUGCCCUUUAUAAAACCGUCAGAUCUUGUGAGCCUUAUUCACUAUCAAGAGAACAGCACGGGAAAAACCCACCCCCAUGAUUCAAUUACUUCCCAUCAGUUCCCUCCCACGACACAUGGGGAUUAAGGGAGCUACAGUUCAAGAUGUGAUUAGGGUGAGGACACAGCCAAACCAUAUCAAGUGCUAUCUUAGCAAAAUCGCCACCAAAAAAAGGAUGAAAAUUACACGGGCCACUAGAUAGACCAUAGGAAGAAUAAUUUUAACAGCACCAGAGCUUGUUCGAUCUCAGAUGGAAACAUUUGCAUCAGGUGACUUAGAUUUUUUUUGCUGCUCUGUACACGUUGGAGAAUGACUGUGAAAGUGCCGUCAGUUUGAUUUGGAGGUGACAAGUAGCUUUUAGCAAGUAGGUGAAUUCACAAAUAUGGAAUCAUGAAUGAUGAGAAUCGGCAAGAUUUCUUCAUUCCUUUGAUGCGGCAUGUAAGCCCCCAGGCACUUAAGAAGGUCAGAGGGAGAUGGAUGAAGAUGAGGAUUACGGUCUCUGCCCUUUAUUAAGAGCCUCCUGUGCAUGGGUAAGGCUGAGCACUUGAUGUUUUGCUGGGGCUGACCACAAGCCCCAGGGAACAGAAGUGUGUAGUCACAGGCAGAGCCAGCCCCCUCAUCUUGCUUUGGUGUAUCCCAUUUUGUAAAUCAAGAGUCAAGACCAUGACCAUGAAGAAUUCAGAGUGGAGACAGAAAAGGGCAAUUUAUUUAGUCCCACCAGCCGGCAACCAGAAUGCCAAAGCUCCAGAAUCCUGCAGCCCUGGGACAAAUGCCCUGAGGAUGCAUAAGCCCACGGAAUCCCAGAAUUCCAAAUGUCCUUCGGCCCAGGUCCAGCUUCCAGUCUGUCCGGUACCAUGAACUACCGCCAAUUCCUCAUGUUCUCUUUGUUUCUAAGGUUCUUGUCUGAGCAGGGAGGCGGUAGGGGUCUGAGUCACUGUGAGGCACACACAGGGAAUGUCUAGAAGGAGGCCUGGGCCUAAGGAGGGGUUCUCAAGAGGGAGAUUAUGCUCUGGCGUUUUGCCAUCAAAGAACUUUAUUUCCUAAUGUUUAUUCUUCAGCUCAGCCUCGGCUAUACCUGCCUAGCUGGUGUUAAACUAAUGAAUCUAACAUUCCCUUCCCUUUGCAUUGGGGUUUGAGUAUGAAACCUGUUUGACAGGGAAUUGGGGGAGAAUUUGUUUGGAUUUGCCUUGACGAGGCCUUUUUCAAAGAUUGGGGAGGCCACUGGUUUCUCUUAAAAGUCAGCAGCGCCCCAGGGAGAAUGUAGGGACUGUCCUUCCACAGUUGUCUUGGAUUUCAGGCUCUCUAGAAACGUCUGGCCACUGGUUGAUUGACAUGGCAUAGACUUUGUAAAAACAAACAAUACGAUAUUGAACCUCAGGGGAACUAGCACUUGAUAACAUGGCUUGCUUAAGGAAGUUAUAAAGAAGAAAAAAGAAAUGGGGAAAAUUCUGUUAAUGGGAAUCAGAACAAUUCUAAGAUUUUCCACUGGGUGGCAUUUUAUUUAAUGUUACUACAUACAGUCACGCAUCACUUAACAAAGGGAUACCCUCUGAGAAAUGUAAAGUUAGGUGAUUUCAUCAUUGUGUGAACAUCAUGGAGUGCACUUACACAAACCUAUAUGGUUUAGCCUACUACACACCUGGGCUACCAGGUCUAGGUACCUGGGUUACCUAUUGCUCCUAAGGUACAAACCUGUGCCACAUGUUGCUGUACUGAACACUGUAGGCAGUUGUAACACAAUGGUAUUUUUGUAUCUAACUGUAUCUUAACAUAGAAAAGAUACAGUAAAAAUGCUGCAUUAUAAUCUUACAUCCUAUCAUACCAUUAUCGUAUAUGCAGCCUGCUGUUGGCUGAAAUGUCAUUAUGCAGUGGAUGGCUAUACAUGCUUCCAGUUGGGGCAGGUCCACAAUCUAAAUUAUUUCUGGGAAUUGCCGUUUAAGACUUCUGAAGAGUGGGGAAAUUUGCUUAGGUGGGAUUCUCUUGCUUUUUACACUAAUUAAAUACAUUUUUAAAAAGUUCCUUUUCCACACUCUGCACACUUCUUACCAUCAUUCUUAAAAAGACUAGAAGUUUGAGCAUAAAGACAAUAUUUUUUUCAUAGUUGCAUACGUCUACCUCGAAUAAUGCCUGGCAAAGAGUUUAUGGGUGCUGCAUACACGCAUGCCUGAUGAAUGAAUGAAUUAGGAAUUACGGCUGCAGCAGUACGCUACUUGUAUGCAUUUAAUUCGAAUUAUCAGACUAUAUAGAUGCUCCUAGACUUAUGAUGGGAUCAUGUCCUGAUAAACCCAUCAUAAAUUAAAUGGAAAAUAUCAAAAGUCAAAAAUGCAUCUAAUUUACCUAAACUGCCAAACAGAAUAGCUUAGCCUGGCCUGCUAAAUGCGCUCAGAACACAUUAGCCUACAGCUGGGCAAAAUCAUCUAACACAAAACCUGUUUUAUAAUAAAGAAUUGAAUAUCUCAUGUAAUUUAUCGAACACCGACCUGAAAAUGAAAACCAGAAUGAUUCGAUACUCAAAAUAUGGUUUCUACUGAAUGGUUACUGCUUUCACACCAUCGUAAGUCAGAAAAUCGUUCAGUCAAACCAUCAUGAGUUGGGGACUGUUUGUAGCAGGGUCAGCAAACAUUUUCUGUAAAUGGCUAGAUAGUACGUGAUUUAGCCUUGGUGGACCAUACUGGUUUUGUCUCAACAGCUUGAUGCUGCUGUUGCAGGUUUGAAAGCAGGCAGAUCAUAUCACAAGGCAUAGCUGUCUUCCCAUAGAACUUUAUUAGCAAAAACAGGCAGUCUGCUGGAUGUGGCCCAUCAGCUGCAGUUUACCCUGAUCUACAUGAAAGCAUACACUGGCAUCAUACAAAUGUUAGAAACCAAUGUAGUAAAAGAUAAAGAGAUUUCAAGACUCUGUGAGUGGUAGACAGCAUGCUCUCCAUUCACCAAAUCCCAUUCCACCUUCCACCUGAACACAUGGGAAAACCACAUUUCCCAGCCUCCCUUGCACUUAGCGGGAGCCUUGUGACUAAAUCUGGCCAAUGAGCUGUGUCCAGAGGCAAAGUCCACCAUGUCCAGACCUGGCCCAUAAGACUUCCUGAACACUGCUCCAUGCUCUCUUCCCUCCCCUGCAGACUGGGUGCAAAUAAUCUAGUGAAGGACUCCAGGGCCCUUCAAGUUGGUGUACUCACUUGCUGGAGUGAGCCUGGAUCCCUGAAUAACUCUGUGGAGGAGAGUCCUCCCCACCCCUACUAUGACCUCAUAAUGGACUGUGAAGGGUUGUAAAAUACACCUGUGCUGUUAAGGCACUGAAAUUCAGGGGUCAUUAGCCUGUCCUCUCUAAUAAUACCAUGUCUGGGCUCAGAUCUGGAUAAAGGAAAGAAACUGAAAAAGAAAUAGAAUUCUCUCCAGGGCUAACAGCCUCCUGUCUGGUGUACCUGCACUUUUUGAUUGGGGAAGAGAGGAACGAGGAGGUCUUAGUGCUCGCAGUCUUAGAAAGUUUAUGUAUAAGAAGCAGUACUGUAGUUUGGGUCUGAGAAACGGGACCUUGAAGAGAGAGUCACUGUGAGGAAAAUGCCCAGAUAAUCAGAGAAGUGGAAGUGGACAAGGUCUCCAUGCUCUCCAGGGAGCAGGUGGAGGCCAUCAAGCAGCUCUGGCAAGAUCCAGGCAUCCAGGAGUGUUACGACAGGAGGAGGGAGUACCAGCUGUCGGACUCUGCCAAAUAUUACCUGACUGACAUUGACCGCAUCGCCACACCAUCAUUCGUGCCUACCCAACAAGAUGUGCUUCGCGUCCGAGUGCCCACCACCGGCAUCAUUGAGUAUCCAUUUGACUUGGAAAACAUCAUCUUUCGGAUGGUGGAUGUUGGUGGCCAACGAUCGGAAAGACGGAAGUGGAUUCACUGCUUUGAGAGUGUCACCUCCAUUAUUUUCUUGGUUGCUCUGAGUGAAUAUGACCAGGUCCUGGCUGAGUGUGACAACGAGAAUCGCAUGGAAGAGAGCAAAGCCUUAUUUAAAACCAUCAUCACCUACCCCUGGUUUCUGAAUUCGUCUGUGAUUUUAUUCUUGAACAAGAAGGAUCUUUUGGAAGAGAAAAUCAUGUACUCUCAUCUAAUUAGCUAUUUCCCAGAAUACACAGGACCGAAACAGGAUGUCAGAGCUGCCAGAGACUUUAUCCUGAAGCUUUACCAAGAUCAGAAUCCUGACAAAGAGAAAGUCAUCUACUCUCACUUCACAUGUGCUACAGAUACAGACAAUAUUCGCUUUGUGUUUGCUGCUGUCAAAGACACAAUUCUACAGCUAAACCUAAGGGAAUUCAACCUUGUCUAAAAGCUGCUGCCCACUCCUCCCCUAUAACAGAAGAUGUGAUUUGCAAACUCCUUGUUUUAUUUGCAAGUGCUUCUGACAUCACCAGAGCCAGCCCCAUGCCAGGAACUAAGGAUGUCAUGUAGAUCGUGGGGACAGAGAUGGGUGAUGGAACUUGGAAGAUAUUUGAGUUUACCAACAUACUUUAAAAGUCCUUACAUCCCAAAUUGUGUUUAUAAUUAUUUUCUUGACUUUUGGCUAUAAGAUUUUGUGUAAUUUUUGAAUUUGGUGUUUUCUAGAAUUUUUAAAAGCCACUUUGAUUUAGUUUUAAAUAUGUUUAAAAAUAGCGAUUAAAAUUAUGUAAGCAAGGAGCCUGUUAGUUUAUAGAUCAUGCCUUCAAACCUCUAGAGUUAAUUUGGGUGACUUUUUUAAAAAUAAGAAUGUUAAUGGGUUUGAAGCUUUUUAUUAAACCUUGUAAUUUAGAGACAUUUUUAAUUGUGUUUCUCACCUCAUGCUGAAGGGUGACUCCUUUAACAUGCCACCAAAGAUUUUUUUUAAACACUUGGUUCUUUUUGUGUGUUAACUUUCUAAGCCAAAUUAAUGGAUAUAUAAGUAUAUCUAAUUUAGCUUUGCCACAGUUUGAUCACCAAGAAGCCAAAGCUGACAUAGAGUAAAUGGGCUCUAGAUAGCAUAUAUGUUUUAUUGGUGAAAAAUGUGUGUGUGUGCACGUGUGUGUGUGUGUACAUUUUUACCCCCAAUGUAUAUGACCAGAUCUUAAAAAUGUAUGAAAUGGCUAGAAGUCCACAUUGUUUGACAAAUGUUACGUAACCCUGCCAAAGUUCUGAUGGCCACCACAGAUUUGCUGUUUGAAUUAUGUAUGCUGUGCCUUUCUGAGGAGGCUAAGAAUAUACCAUUCUGCUAUUA